CUUUUCCUCUCCAGAGGGGCCGAUUAGGGAGAGAGACCAGAAAUGAGUGGAAUGCUAUCUUAAGCCAAAAAAAACUAUUAUAAUUUUUAUUUAGUACUACUUAAAUGAAGAAAGAUAAAAAAAGAAACAAAAUUCCAAUUGAUAAUUAUCCCAUUCAGACAUUAGUGAAUAUGUCACUCAAUCCAAGUCGACCUUCCUCAUCAGAGUUGGUGGAACUUCAUGUUUUUUAUGUCCCUGAAGGAUCAUGGAACUAUAAGCUAAAUACCAUUUCAACAGAAGUUGUUAACAAAUUCAUUUCAGCUGGAUUUCUAAGAGUAUCUCCUCAACUUACUUUACGAGCCCUGAGGGAGCGUCUUGGUGAGUUCCUGGGUGAAGAUGCUAUUGCAGAAAAAUUUUUAUUUCUGAAAUGCAUUGGAAAUAAUUUAGCUGUGGUGAAGGAAAAGCAAGAAUCAGAACUGAAACUCAAAUCAUUUGCUCCUCCAUAUGCUCUUCAACCAGAAUUAUAUUUGCUUCCUGUAAUGGACCAUUUAGGAAAUGUUUAUUCACCAUCAACAGUUAUUUUAGAUGAGCGGCAGACUAAUAAUGGUGUUAAUGAGGCUGAUGGAACAAUCCACAGACCAAUUAGUGUAACUUUGUUCAAGGAGGAACUUGGAAGAGAUCCCAGUUUGUUAGAAAACACUUUGAAAGAGCUUCCUAACAAGAAUCAGGAAGAAGCUGGGGGAAAAGCCACUGCAGAAAAAAGCCAAAUUGCAAAAAAUCAAAUUGGAAAUUCUGAGUUGCCAGGAUCAUUGGAAGAUUCAAAUAAUGAUUGCUUUGGCACUAAAAAAAGUCAGUGUCUUUGGGAAAAUGAAGAUGAUACAGCUAUCAGUAGAAGACAGGACAAUCAGACAGCUGAAAAAGAGUACAUCACCCUACCAGAUCACCCUUCACUUCCUUGUCAACCUGUUCUUUCUUCAGGAAUAACUGAUAUAUCUUUAUUACAAACUGAAAGAGAGAAGAUUAUCAAACAAAUGAAACAAGUAAAGGAAGAAAGAAGGUAUCUGGAAAGAAAUAGAGAAGAACUAGUAAAAACGGUUGAAAAGCUAUUUGAACAAAGCAAAUUAAAACGAUAUCAUGCCUACAAUGGUUGGAAGAAAAAAUACUUGGAAACAAAGAAAGUCACAGCAUCAAUGGAGGAGGUUUUAACAAAACUUCGAGAAGAUUUGGAACUCUACUAUAAAAAACUGCUCAUGCAACUUGAAGCCAGGGAGAUCAAGAUGAGACCAAAGAAUCUGGCAAACAUCACAGACUCCAAGAAUUACCUAAUAAUCCAGAUCACUGAGGUACAGCAUGCAAUUGACCAGCUUAAGAGAAAACUAGAUACUGACAAAAUGAAACUCAUAGUAGAAGUUAAGUUGCUAGAAGUGUGCCUGGCUAGGAGGUCUACAGAAGAUUUUGUUUAUGAUGAAUCAGCCAAGUCAAAAGGGAGCAUUGGCUGCUGCAAUACAUUCUGACCAGAUCUGACUUUGUUCAUCAUAAGACAUCACAAAGAGGAAGUCACAAGCAUCUGCGAUUCCAGUAUAAUUAUAGCAUCUUCUGUCUAUGUUCUUUGGAGACCAAGCUACAUCAAAGGUUACCUGUGGAAAAAAAUCUUACUAUUUUAUGUAAUAUGAUCACGUGUGCAUAUUACGUCAGAUUUUUAAAAUUAUAUAUAUUUUUUACCUUAUACUACACAAGGAAAAGGAACUGCUUACAGUAUAUGAAUGUAGGGUUUGACACACAUAGAACUUGAACCAUUCUAAGAAAUAUUUUUUGCUUACACUUGACUGAGUCAGACAUAUAUUUGGACAUACAAUGACCAGGAGCAAGACACUAUAUAGAAGAUGGCCUUCAAACUCAAAAUGUCUUCAAACGCUAGGCUGGUACCUCAGCUGAUUAAAAGAAGCAGGUAUAAUGACAACAGGGUAUGGUGAUGCCCCUGAGCAACUAGAGAGUAAAGGCACACUAAAAGAAUUCAAAUACAAAAGUUUUUAAAAUAUUGUGCAGGUUAAAUAUGUCACCUGUUGGCACAACCUGACUGGGUUGGGAGUUUCAGCCUGAUUCACAAUCACCUUAUAUGGUAGAUUUGGCCCAAUAUUACAGUUAAGACAAUAGUGGUGUCUUACGGCCUACAGGUAUAGAUUAAUCAAGUCAAAAUGUUGAAUAAAUCAUUUAAAUGAUCUUAUUUUACGGAAAUAUUCAAAUAAAUGUUGAGUAUUAUCUUUCUUUUUUGGGGGGGAUGGAGUCUUGCUCUGUCACCCAGGGUGGAGUGCAGUGGCGCAAUCUCAGCUCACUGCAACCUCUGCCUCCUGGGUUCAAGUGAUUCUCCUGCCUCAGCCUCCCACAUAGCUGGGAUUACAGGCAUGCGCCACCACGCCCAGCUAAUUUUUUUGUAUUUUUAGUAGAGACAGGGUUUUGCCAUGUUGCCCAGGCUGGUCUCAAACUCCUGACCUCAGCUGAUCUGCCGAUCUCAGCCUCCCAAAGUGCUUACAGGCGUGAGCCACCACACCCAGCCUUAUCUUUCAUUUUGAAUAGUGAGCCAGCCUUCAACAAGAAUGUGUCUCUUUAUGUUUAUUGCCUUAACCAAAUAUUAAUUAGCCUUAUUUUAUACAUGUACAAAUGUUCUAAAACUUCAUUAAAGGUUGUUUUCCCCCCUUAAUUAGGCACUCAAUAAACACUGAUUAUUUUAAAAACUGAGAUACUUUAGGUAACAUUUUUAUACUUUGAACAAUUUAUUCUAGCAAAACUCUUUUUAGGACUUCUUCAAAGUUCCCUUUAUAAUUCCGUGAAUAUUAGCACUUUAUAAUUAUAAGCUUUGCUCAGUAGUUUUCCAACAAAAUAAGUUAUGAAAUAAAAUUAUUACAUAUUUGUUCCUAUUUUAUCACUGCCUCUUAUUACAAAAUGAGAGGUAUAUUAUAGUAAUAGAGAAAAAUAAAUGACUACCUCUAAGCAAGUAAAUUUCCAA